AUUCGUGAGGGGUUUGUAAUGCAGGGCUGAGGAGUGUCCGAAGAGAAUGGGCAGGUGAGCGGUGAGACAGUUGUUCUUCCAGAAGCUUUGCAGUGAAAGGAAUCAAAGAAAUGGAGCCGUGUAUCAGCAGCCAGACUGCCUUCCGGGUCACUGCCAUGGAGGAGCCGCAGUCAGAUCCUAGCGUCGAGCCCCCUCUGAGUCAGGAAACAUUUUCAGACCUAUGGAAACUACUUCCUGAAAACAACGUUCUGUCCCCCUUGCCGUCCCAAGCAAUGGAUGAUUUGAUGCUGUCCCCGGACGAUAUUGAACAAUGGUUCACUGAAGACCCAGGUCCAGAUGAAGCUCCCAGAAUGCCAGAGGCUGCUCCCCCCGUGGCCCCUGCACCAGCAGCUCCUACACCGGCGGCCCCUGCACCAGCCCCCUCCUGGCCCCUGUCAUCUUCUGUCCCUUCCCAGAAAACCUACCAGGGCAGCUACGGUUUCCGUCUGGGCUUCUUGCAUUCUGGGACAGCCAAGUCUGUGACUUGCACGUACUCCCCUGCCCUCAACAAGAUGUUUUGCCAACUGGCCAAGACCUGCCCUGUGCAGCUGUGGGUUGAUUCCACACCCCCGCCCGGCACCCGCGUCCGCGCCAUGGCCAUCUACAAGCAGUCACAGCACAUGACGGAGGUUGUGAGGCGCUGCCCCCACCAUGAGCGCUGCUCAGAUAGCGAUGGUCUGGCCCCUCCUCAGCAUCUUAUCCGAGUGGAAGGAAAUUUGCGUGUGGAGUAUUUGGAUGACAGAAACACUUUUCGACAUAGUGUGGUGGUGCCCUAUGAGCCGCCUGAGGUUGGCUCUGACUGUACCACCAUCCACUACAACUACAUGUGUAACAGUUCCUGCAUGGGCGGCAUGAACCGGAGGCCCAUCCUCACCAUCAUCACACUGGAAGACUCCAGUGGUAAUCUACUGGGACGGAACAGCUUUGAGGUGCGUGUUUGUGCCUGUCCUGGGAGAGACCGGCGCACAGAGGAAGAGAAUCUCCGCAAGAAAGGGGAGCCUCACCACGAGCUGCCCCCAGGGAGCACUAAGCGAGCACUGCCCAACAACACCAGCUCCUCUCCCCAGCCAAAGAAGAAACCACUGGAUGGAGAAUAUUUCACCCUUCAGGACCAGACCAGCUUUCAAAAAGAAAAUUGUUAAAGAGAGCAUGAAAAUGGUUCUAUGACUUUGCCUGAUACAGAUGCUACUUGACUUACGAUGGUGUUACUUCCUGAUAAACUCGUCGUAAGUUGAAAAUAUUAUCCGUGGGCGUGAGCGCUUCGAGAUGUUCCGAGAGCUGAAUGAGGCCUUGGAACUCAAGGAUGCCCAGGCUGGGAAGGAGCCAGGGGGGAGCAGGGCUCACUCCAGCCACCUGAAGUCCAAAAAGGGUCAGUCUACCUCCCGCCAUAAAAAACUCAUGUUCAAGACAGAAGGGCCUGACUCAGACUGACAUUCUCCACUUCUUGUUCCCCACUGACAGCCUCCCACCCCCAUCUCUCCCUCCCCUGCCAUUUUGGGUUUUGGGUCUUUGAACCCUUGCUUGCAAUAGGUGUGCGUCAGAAGCACCCAGGACUUCCAUUUGCUUUGUCCCGGGGCUCCACUGAACAAGUUGGCCUGCACUGGUGUUUUGUUGUGGGGAGGAGGAUGGGGAGUAGGACAUACCAGCUUAGAUUUUAAGGUUUUUACUGUGAGGGAUGUUUGGGAGAUGUAAGAAAUGUUCUUGCAGUUAAGGGUUAGUUUACAAUCAGCCACAUUCUAGGUAGGGGCCCACUUCACCGUACUAACCAGGGAAGCUGUCCCUCACUGUUGAAUUUUCUCUAACUUCAAGGCCCAUAUCUGUGAAAUGCUGGCAUUUGCACCUACCUCACAGAGUGCAUUGUGAGGGUUAAUGAAAUAAUGUACAUCUGGCCUUGAAACCACCUUUUAUUACAUGGGGUCUAGAACUUGACCCCCUUGAGGGUGCUUGUUCCCUCUCCCUGUUGGUCGGUGGGUUGGUAGUUUCUACAGUUGGGCAGCUGGUUAGGUAGAGGGAGUUGUCAAGUCUCUGCUGGCCCAGCCAAACCCUGUCUGACAACCUCUUGGUGAACCUUAGUACCUAAAAGGAAAUCUCACCCCAUCCCACACCCUGGAGGAUUUCAUCUCUUGUAUAUGAUGAUCUGGAUCCACCAAGACUUGUUUUAUGCUCAGGGUCAAUUUCUUUUUUCUUUUUUUUUUUUUUUUUUCUUUUUCUUUGAGACUGGGUCUCGCUUUGUUGCCCAGGCUGGAGUGGAGUGGCGUGAUCUUGGCUUACUGCAGCCUUUGCCUCCCCGGCUCGAGCAGUCCUGCCUCAGCCUCCGGAGUAGCUGGGACCACAGGUUCAUGCCACCAUGGCCAGCCAACUUUUGCAUGUUUUGUAGAGAUGGGGUCUCACAGUGUUGCCCAGGCUGGUCUCAAACUCCUGGGCUCAGGCGAUCCACCUGUCUCAGCCUCCCAGAGUGCUGGGAUUACAAUUGUGAGCCACCACGUCCAGCUGGAAGGGUCAACAUCUUUUACAUUCUGCAAGCACAUCUGCAUUUUCACCCCACCCUUCCCCUCCUUCUCCCUUUUUAUAUCCCAUUUUUAUAUCGAUCUCUUAUUUUACAAUAAAACUUUGCUGCCA